GGACUUCUGCCAAGCACCGGCUCAUGUGAGGCUCGCGGCACAGCGUUCUCUGGGCUCCCCAGAAGCCAGCCUUUCGCUCCCGGACCCGGCAGCCCGAGCAGGAGCCGUGGGACCGGGCGCCAGCACCCUCUGCGGCGUGUCAUGGGCCCGCGCCGCCGGAGCCGAAAGCCCGAGGCCCCGAGGAGGCGCAGCCCGAGCCCGACCCCGACCCCCGGCCCCUCCCGGCGGGGCCCCUCCUUAGGCGCUUCCUCCCAUCAACACAGUCGGCGGAGACAAGGUUGGCUAAAGGAGAUCCGAAAGCUUCAGAAGAGCACACACCUCUUGAUAAGGAAGCUGCCCUUCAGCCGCCUGGCAAGAGAAAUAUGUGUUAAAUUCACUCGUGGUGUGGACUUCAAUUGGCAAGCCCAGGCCCUAUUGGCCCUACAAGAGGCAGCAGAAGCAUUUCUAGUUCAUCUCUUUGAGGACGCCUAUCUCCUCACCUUACAUGCAGGCCGAGUUACUCUCUUCCCAAAGGAUGUGCAACUGGCCCGGAGGAUCCGGGGCCUUGAGGAGGGACUCGGCUGAGCUCCUGCACCCAGUGUUUCUGUCAGUCUUUCCUGCUCAGCCAGGGGGGAUGAUACCGGGGACUCUCCAGAGCCAUGACUAGAUCCAAUGGAUUCUGCGAUGCUGUCUGGACUUUGCUGUCUCUGAACAGUAUGUGUGUGUUGCUUUAAAUAUUUUUCUUUUUUUUGAGAAGGAGAAGACUGCAUGACUUUCCUCUGUAACAGAGGUAAUAUAUGAGACAAUCAACACCGUUCCAAAGGCCUGAAAAUAAUUUUCAGAUAAAGAGACUCCAAGGUUGACUUUAGUUUGUGAGUUACUCAUGUGACUAUUUGAGGAUUUUGAAAACAUCAGAUUUGCUGUGGUAUGGGAGAAAAGGCUAUGUACUUAUUAUUUUAGCUCUUUCUGUAAUAUUUACAUUUUUUACCAUAUGUACAUUUGUACUUUUAUUUUACACAUAAGGGAAAAAAUAAGACCACUUUGAGCAGUUGCCUGGAAGGCUGGGCAUUUCCAUCAUAUAGACCUCUGCCCUUCAGAGUAGCCUCACCAUUAGUGGCAGCAUCAUGUAACUGAGUGGACUGUGCUUGUCAACGGAUGUGUAGCUUUUCAGAAACUUAAUUGGGGAUGAAUAGAAAACCUGUAAGCUUUGAUGUUCUGGUUACUUCUAGUAAAUUCCUGUCAAAAUCAAUUCAGAAAUUCUAACUUGGAGAAUUUAACAUUUUACUCUUGUAAAUCAUAGAAGAUGUAUCAUAACAGUUCAGAAUUUUAAAGUACAUUUUCGAUGCUUUUAUGGGUAUUUUUGUAGUUUCUUUGUAGAGAGAUAAUAAAAAUCAAAAUAUUUAAUGAAAA